UUGUUCCUCUCUUUGUAUCACUACUAUUUUAAUGUCUCUACUAGUUCUCUUAUUUUUGUCAUUUCUGAGUUGAUUUUAUUUUUCUCACUAUGGCCAUAUUCUCCUACUUCUUUGAAUAUCUGGUAUGCAAAUUAUACCUAGUAUGGAUAUUAUAUCAAGACCCUGUCGCAAUAUGGAUACCUAAAAGAAAAUAACAAUGUUUACCAGUUUGCUCUAAGCCUUUCUUAGCUCUUUUGCUUGUUUCUCAAGAACAAGCACAGAGGGUGGAGCUCAACCAAGACUGAAGUUAAAGAUGUAGAAAGAUUGAGAUGGGAAGUAAUUAAGUUGAGGAGCUCUGAUACAAUGGUAUUUCUCUUUUUAAUCAUGUAAGAUGCAAGCCCAAGAUAAUAUGUUGGGAAAGUUGAAGGCGAAUGUCUUGAGAAAUAUGAAAUGCACCCAAGGCUAUGGCUGGGUGAUAGAAAUAACUAAAAAGUUUUAAAAGGAUUGUUUUAUAGCUGGUCCUUGCUGAGGUUAGGGGAUAGGCCUGGAAAAAUUGAGCAGUGGUAUUGCCCAGGCAGGACUCCUCAUGACAUUCUCCAGAUCCCUAAGUUUUUCCAAGUUUCCAAGCAUUUCCUUGGCCAGCAAGUCAUCUCGCAGCACAGAUCCUACUCUCUUUCAGUCAGUCAUUCCACAACUCUACAAAGCAUUUUUCUCCAUCAAAUGGGAACUUUUGGGGUUCUGCAUAAUUUUUCAGGGUUCCACCACUUUUGACUCUUUCUGGAUACCUUGUAAGGAUAUUAUAACUCUUUAAUUCAUGUCCUUGAUUUUCUCUUUUAACUUUUAAUACUGUUCAUUGCCUGUUUACCUCUUUCACCCUCUUCUUUUCACUUCCGCCCUCUUUCUUGUGUAAGUAUAUAAUCAUCCUUUUUUUCUUCCUCGAAUCUCAGUUCUCGGGAGUAACAUAUACAAUUCAUUCUUACUUCCAGUCUUUUAUUCCUAAGUUCCUUAUCUCUAGUUCUCUUGCAUAUUUGUGGCAAUUAUUAGUUUUUUUCCAAAAAUCCAUUCUCCCUUUUUCCUGUACAUGUAUCUUUCCAGCUUGACCACAUUUCCCAGCUUCCCUGGCAGCUAGGUGAAGCAAUGUAACUAAACUUUUGCCUGUAAAAUAUGAGCAGAAGUUAUGUGCACAAUAUCUGCCUCACUUGCUUAAAAUAAAUUGUAUUAUUUGAGCUUUCUAUAUUGUCCCUUUUUACAACUAAAAUGUAGAGGUUAUGGCAACUUUUAUGGUAAAGAGAAUCAUCACGUAGGAGAUCAAGAAUCAUUGAUUUGAGAGGAACCUAAAUCCUUUAAUGACUUAGUGGAGCAAGACUGCCCCAUCAGUCUGGAAGCUACCCCACAACUUAUGUAUAUCUUCAGAUUGUUGAGCAAAAGAGAAAAAAUGAAGCCACUAUAUAUUUAGGUCUCUUCAUGUUAACAGUUUAGCUUUUAACCUAACACACAUUUAUUCCUGAAUGGUAGCAUAUUAUUAACAUCACAGGAAGGGAAUUCCUUGUUCAUGGAUCUUUUAUUUUGUUGAAAUAAAGGUAAUCUGCUUGGGCUUAAUACUGCCAAGGCAGAAUUUUUUGGAAUAAUUAUUUCUAUAGAUGACCCAUUCAUAAUGACAACUAACAUGGUUUCUAAAAUGGAUUCAUGUACGUCAUCUUAUUUAGUCCCCGCAAAAAUUCUGAAGGUAGGUAUAAUUAUUCCCAUUCUAUAUAUUGAAAAAUUGGGAUUCAGAGAGACUACGGACUUAUACAAGUUUCUGCAGCUAUUUAAGAAACAGAGUAAAGUCUCAAAGCCAUUAAUGAACUGUUUAGUUUAGUGCUGCUUAGUAAAAUUAGAACUGUUUGAAGUGCGUUUUAAUAGUAAACCCAUCGAUAUUUAGUCAGCUCUCUGCUUGCUAACUAAUAUGGAAGAAAAAACAUACAUCUACGUACAUCCUGAAUUGGGAGAAGGGAAAUAAAAUAUUGCCAAUCCCCUUUCCUGUAUUAGGUACUGUGAUAAGGCGAUAAGGCUUUUCAUUAUUAUAAAUGAGUCCUGGAGAGGUUAAGCGCAGUCACCCAAAGUCACAUGACCAGUAACUUUCAGAGAUUUUACCCCAGGUCUGGAAAGACUCUGAAGCCCAUGUUAUUGCCUCCAGAGCCUGGUGGAGAACCCCUGAAUGGGACAGAGACUCAGCAGACAGAGUGGUCCUUUCCUUCCAGGGAGUCAGGGAAGGUUUGGUAGGGGAGAUAGAGUUAGAUCUGGGUGGGAUUUGGAUGAAAUGAGAUCAAGCAGGGAUAAAUAAGAUCCAAGCUGUUUAUGAGGGACAGGGAGAGGCCAGCUCUGUUAGAAAGAGUGGUUUAUACAGAGAAGCAUGGAAACAUUUGCUCCAUGCCUCGCCUUCCAUGGAUAGCAGUCCAGAAAUGCUACUUGCCUGCCUGACAGUCUUUCUCCAGUCCCCAGGUGUGGACACGUUCUGAGCACCUGAGCCUGGGUCUGCCCUGACCCAGAUUCUGUGAGCUGGGACAGAGAAUGUGUCCUGCUGUCCCUCCUCCCCCACUUGGGCCCACACCCUUUUCUACACAUUUGGAUUAGAAAUCUGAAUUGGCCUUUCUGUGAACCCCAAUGACAGGCAAGUCCCCAGUAAAGAAGCACUUAAUUUAAUUGCUCCUUCAGGGUCCACUUAGAGUAAUAGUUGUGAACAGCUCUCCCUAGUGUCUCCCACAGGCAGUGACAAAUGUUGCUAAAGAUAAGUCACAAAUUCUUGGCAAGGCCAUCUUAAAUAUGGGAAGGAAACCUUGUUCAGUCCUGAACAGUCCUGUUCAGACUGAUCUUAUCACAGGUUGCACACUGCCUCAAUGUCACCAUGUUUCUACCCUCAGUUGUGCUUGGCAGAGAGAGGACAGCUAUACAUAAAGUCUGUUCACUCUACAAAGGUGAAAUCAUUUUUUUUAAGGUAAUUAUGAUUGUUCUGAGGAUGGUGAUUGAGUGACAUUUAAAAAAUGGGAAAAGUUCUACUCAUAACUCUGUCUGCUUAAUUUGCUUAUAUAAAAGACUUAAUGGUUUUUGUUGAGUUGAUCCAGAGUCAGUAACAUUUGAAUAUGUGUUAUUACCAUUUGAUCAGUAACAAAACAACAGGGUAAGUGGGAUGCCAAAUGUGGCUGAGAGUUUAGGGUUUACAUUCCACACCCCAGCCUUAAAUACGUUUGUAUAAAUUAUUGGUUGAUUUUUCUUUUUCAUGGCUUUUCUUUGACAUUUGAUGGGGCUGGAUUUAUGGAGGCAACCAACAAAUUACACAGCAAUGAAUUCUGGACUGUAGUCCCACAGCCUUGAGCCUAGAUACUAGCUGUGUCACUAAUACUCUGUGUGACCAGGAAGCUUGAGUGCCCAAGGGUUUGAUAAAUGUGGAAAAUAACCGCUGUUCGAAUAUCCUGUUGGCCUGCUGAAGAAAUGACUGGCUGAGGCUGUAAAGAAAUCUUGUGGUCAUUCUCAUGGAAAGAGGAUUGGAGCCCCGAUUCUUUGAUCUCAUUAUUGACCAGUUGAUUGAGAAGACUGUCCUCCUGUCCCCACCCAAUCACAAUAAGUGGGUAAUUACCUGAGGGCUAAUUUGCUCCUUGAAUGUGAAUACAUUUGUGGAAAUUUCCUUGUGCUCAGCACCUGUUCAAAACAUCCAUUUGUAUUGCAGAGCUAUUGUUUUUCUAAUCUCAUUGUGGAGCUAAGAGAGAGAUUGUGUUUAAGGUUUCCUUCGUAAUAGGUUUUCUUGCUCCAGGAAGGAUGCGUGACAGACUCUGCACACUGCUGCUUGGUAGGUGUUCAGUGAUGGAUGCGUUUUCCAUCUCCCAGGUACAGCUGCAGCUGUGCUGACUCUGGUGCGUUUGUAAUAUGCACUGUGGAGUGCACCAUGAUUUCAUGAUGGCUGGAGAAAUCUGGUGGCUAGAAUUCUAGGGAGGAGGACAUGAGUCGGAAGUGCAGAAACCUCACACUGGGACAUUGAUGGAGAAAAUCCAAUUCUGUCCCUGGAGUUAAAGAGGAGUCACUCACUGGGCCAUCAUAAGAGCAAAUAAAGUUACAGUUAUUUCUUCAGAUCCACAACUCAAACUCAGCGAAAGUAAUUAUUCACUCUUUUUGUCCCAAACAAUAAUGAAAUCAGCUAAAGCAUAUUGUAUUUAUUACUUCCACUCAAGUUAUUGAGCUGUUCUGACACCUUGUUGCUGGGAAGAUACACAGAUGGAACACCAUCAUUUCCAUUGAUUCUGAUCAUACCCCACGCUAAUAUAGCCUUAUUGCUCUGAGUCAUAGGGAUUUUAUGCUUGCCUAUUCAAAAAACAGUUUUUACCUUAUUAAAAGGUGAUAUGACCUGAGCUGGAGAUGAUGUUUGGUCAUUUUGUGUAAACCUUUUAAUAUUUUAGUGGUAAAUACAUUUCUUGAAUCUUGACAAAAACAUAAUUAAAAUGAACAUAUUUAAAAUGGACAUCUUCCAAAUGUUCAUUUUUAAAACAAACAUCUUCCAAAUGUUCAUUUUUAAAAUGAAUAUCUUCGUUAACUUUUUUUUUUUUUUUUGAGACGGAGUCUCGCUCUGUCACCCAGGCUGGAGUGCAGUGGCGCGAUCUCGGCUCACUGCAAGCUCCGCCUCCCGGGUUCACGCCAUUCUCCUGCCUCAGCCUCCAGAGUAGCUAGGACUACAGGCGCCCGCCACCACGCCCGGCUAAUUUUUGUAUUUUUAGUAGAGACGGGGUUUCACCGUGUUAGCCAGGAAGGUCUCGAUCUCCUGACCUUCUGAUCCACCCUCCACGGCCUCCCAAAGUGCUGGGAUUACAGGCGUGAGUCACCACGCCCAGCCUCUUCCUUAACUUUUAAUGAAUAAAGAGUUGAAAGGGAAAAACCAAAUGUGCACUAUGCUGAUUUUAUCUUGAGCUGUACAGAAUGUGCAGUAACUUAAGAAUAUAAGUCAUUCUGCUGUUAUUCAUACUAGCCUAUUCUUUAGCAUUAUUUAAACACACAUAUUUGAGUGUCUACACACUGCCUGCUAGGCAGGGGGCUGGGUGCCAAGAAGGGAUGUCCAGAGAUAAACGGGCAUAUGUGUUAAUCUUUUAGGGCACAGUCCAGUAACCUGAUCAAGGAGUGACGUGUAUUGUGUACUAGGAUAGAAGUCAGUAUCAGAGGAAACACAAAGGAAAGAGUGGUACUUUCUCCCCAGGGAAGGGAUGCUCAGAAAGAGGGGGCUGAUUAUGUCCCUGGUUCAUGAGAAAAAGGGCAUUCCUGGCUCAGGGAGUGGGAAGAACAAAACCAAGAAAUCCUGGAAUGGCUUGGUGCAUCAGCCAGUCUGUGAGUGCAGGGCAUGGCUGGAGUUCUGGCUUUAAGAUGAGUGGGAAGAAAGGCUGGAGAGGAGGUGGAUCCAGGAAAAGUUGCUGGGAGCAUUUAUUCUUUUGGCAAUGGGAAGCCAUGGAAGAACUGUUGUAAGGAGGAUUCUGUGUGAUACAUCUGCCUUUUAGAGAGGUCAUUUUAUAGAAAAAGUAGAAAAUACAGACCAGCAAAAAUUUAAAAAGUGAAAACAAUCACUGUUCAAGCUCUGGUCUAGCACUCACCAGUGUUUUUCCUACAGGUGCAUAUACAAACAUGCUUUUACAUUUUAUUUUUAUUUUAAAUUUUUCACUAUCCUCAAUAUCAGUGGAAACAAAUCUGCUUUUUUAAUUUUUUUUUUAAAAAUGAGAUCCUAUUGUACACAUUAUUUUAAAUUUUUUUUCAUUCUUUCCUUUUUUUAAAAUUAAAACAAUUUUUUUUGAGACAGUCUCACUCUGUCGCCCAGGCUAGAGUGCAGCAUCGUGGUCUCAGCUCACCGAAACCUUGCCUCCCAGGUUCAAGCGAUUCUCCUGCCUCAGCCUUCCAAGUAGCUGGGAUUACAGACAUCCACCACCACCGUGUCAGGUUAAUUUUUGUAUUUUUAGUAGAGAAUGGGGUUUCACCAUUUUGGACAGGCUGGUCUUGAAUUCCUGGCUUCAAGUGAUCUGCCUGCCUCGGCCUCCCAAAGUGUCAUUCUCCUUUUAAAAGCAUCAGUAAAACACUUCCAAAGCAUUACUUUGAUAAUUAGACAGCAUUUAUAUCAAUUUACCAUAAUAUACUCACGUUUAAGGGUAUAGAUUGUUUUAAAUUUCCACUAUUAUAAAUAGUGCUGCUCUGACACCUUCAGGAUGCUUUUUAUUAUUCCUUAGGAUACAUUUCUGGAAGAGGAAGUUCCGGCUCAAAUGGAAUACAUAUUUUAAAAGGCCUGCAUCUUUGCAGCCAUUCUAAUGCUAGUUAAUAUCAUGCUUUUCUAACUUUGCCAGAUCAUGGAUGAUGAAGACUAGAUCAUGGAUUUAAUUUGCAUUUGUUUGAGGUUGAAUGAUGCUUCAUGAGUUUAACUGGCCAACUGUAUUUAUUUUUUAUAAACUGAGUGUUCACGCCUUUUUUCUACUGUAAUAUUGGGGUGUUUAUCUUAAUCAAUAUGCCCUAAUGCAUCUCUAUCUUUCAUGCAGUGAUGUGAGGUGUGGAAGAAACACGGGAGCAGCCUUCCUCAGGACACCUCUUGUUUAUCUCUCUAGCUCUGAAAUCACAUGAAGCUGUGGAUGGAGAGUCACCUGAUAGUCCCAGAAACCCGUCCCAGCCCAAGGAUGAUGAGUAACCAGACGUUGGUAACCGAGUUCAUCCUGCAGGGCUUUUCGGAGCACCCAGAAUACCGGGUGUUCUUAUUCAGCUGUUUCCUCUUCCUCUACUCUGGGGCCCUCACAGGUAAUGUCCUCAUCACCUUGGCCAUCACGUUCAACCCUGGGCUCCACGCUCCUAUGUACUUUUUCUUACUCAACUUGGCUACUAUGGACAUUAUCUGCACCUCUUCCAUCAUGCCCAAGGCGCUGGCCAGUCUGGUGUCGGAAGAGAGCUCCAUCUCCUACGGGGGCUGCAUGGCCCAGCUCUAUUUCCUCACGUGGGCUGCAUCCUCAGAGCUGCUGCUCCUCACGGUCAUGGCCUAUGACCGGUACGCAGCCAUCUGCCACCCGCUGCAUUACAGCAGCAUGAUGAGCAAGGUGUUCUGCAGCGGGCUGGCCACAGCCGUGUGGCUGCUCUGCGCCGUCAACACGGCCAUCCACACGGGGCUGAUGCUGCGCUUGGAUUUCUGUGGCCCCAAUGUCAUUAUCCAUUUCUUCUGCGAGGUCCCUCCCCUGCUGCUUCUCUCCUGCAGCUCCACCUACGUCAACGGUGUCAUGAUUGUCCUGGCGGAUGCUUUCUACGGCAUAGUGAACUUCCUGAUGACCAUCGCGUCCUAUGGCUUCAUCGUCUCCAGCAUCCUGAAGGUGAAGACUGCCUGGGGGAGGCAGAAAGCCUUCUCCACCUGCUCUUCCCACCUCACCGUGGUGUGCAUGUAUUACACCGCUGUCUUCUACGCCUACAUAAGCCCGGUCUCUGGCUACAGCGCAGGGAAGAGCAAGUUGGCUGGCCUGCUGUACACUGUGCUGAGUCCUACCCUCAACCCCCUCAUCUAUACUUUGAGAAACAAGGAGGUCAAAGCAGCCCUCAGGAAGCUUUUCCCUUUCUUCAGAAAUUAACUUGUGUCUUCUGAAGUUUUUGUCCUUGGAGACUGCAGUUUUAGUGGAGUCUGAUGAGCAAGUUUCUGGACUGGGAGGUAAAUAGACUUGUUUUUUCUAACCCAGCAGAACCUGUGCAUGGAUGAGCUGGGAGUGCUGGUUCCCUGAGACUUGGUGAUGGGGGGAUUGCGGUAGGUGUGACCCACCAGCCUCUGAGACACCAGAUCUCUUGGUCUGACUCCAAGGUGGUGUCAGUGCUGAGUUGGCAGAGAAACACAGGGCCUAGGAGGAGAAAAGUGUUCCUUGUGUUUUCAACUCAUAGCCACAUCAAACAUUUUCCUUUUGUAUGUACAACACUCAGGGUGUAAAUUCUAAAAUCACACCUAGAAUUCAGCUGUGUGGGUCUAAAAAGUUAGGCAGAAUUGUGGACCCCACAGCCCCUGAAGGGUUGUCAGACUGAAGCUUUGUUUUAAGGUGACCACUGGCCUCUAGGAAACCUUCUACCCCCAUUAUCUUACCUCAACUGUUUCCUCUGGAGCCACUUGGACUUCAAAAAUAGUUUGAUUUUAAUGCAAACUGUUGUUUCUGCUUUUGUCUUUUCUUCUUACUAACACUUCAGAUUCUGAGUAUCUGACCUACCUAAUUGGCCUGGAGCGAGGACAGCUGCCAUGAGUCAGCUCUAAUAAGUUAAACGGCAUUGUAGUAAGGCAUUGCUAUCCUUCCAUUGUUUCAGAUAAAACUGGGUGAACGAAUCCUCUGUGUCUAAUAAAGACAGGUCUUGUGCUUGUGCUCCAUGCUAUUACAAAACUGCACUGGAAAAUCCAUUAUCUUUAUCAUGAUCCAUUAAAGAUGACAGAACUAAGAUGUGAAUGUUUAGUUGUAUCUUGGAAUUGAAUAGAAACAUAUCAUUCGAUAUGUGUGUGAAGCUGAGAGUAGAGUUUGAUAUUUGAUUUAGAUGGGAUGGUUCUUCAUCCAGUAUUCUCAUUAUCAUUCAUCAGAAGCUCAUUGACUCAAGUAUUUGAUGAAUUGUAGCUGACUGUAGCUUUGGCACGUAGAUUCUUACAGACAGUUUAAUCUCUUCUAAGUGAAUUCUGAGUCCCAAAUAACAUGUUGAAACCCUCAGUGGUCUCACUUUCCAAUAAACAUGGCUUUGAAAACCAGCA